UUUUUUUUUUAAGGUACAGGGUCUUGGCUGGGCACGGUGGCUCAUGCCUGUAAUCCCUGCAUUUUGGGAGGCUGAGGCAGGCGGAUCACCUGAAGUCAAGAGUUUGCGACCAGCCUGAUCAACAUGGAGAAACCCUGUCUCUACUAAAAAUACAAAAUUAGCUGGGCCUGGUGGCGCAUGCCUGUAAUCCCAGCUACUCGGGAGGCUGAGACAGGAGAAUCGCUUGAACCUGGGAGGCGGAGGUUGCGGUGAGCCGAGAUCGUGCCAUUGCACUCCAGCCUGGGCAACAAGAGUGAAACUCCAUCUCAGGAAAAAAAAAAAAAAAAAAAAAAUCUCUGGCUGGGUGCCGUGGCUGACGCCUGUAAUCCCAGCACUUUGGGAGGCCGAGGCAGGUAACUCAUGAGGUCAGGAGUUCAAGACCAGCCUGGUCAAGAUGGUGAAACCCCGUCUCUACUAAAAAUACAAAAAAAAAUUAGCUGGGCGCAGUGGCAGGUGCCUGUAAUCCCAGCUACUUGGGAGGCUGAGGCAAGAGAAUGGCUUGAAGCCAGGGGAAGGAGGUUGCCGUGAGCCGAGAUCGCGCCACUGCUCUCCAGCCUAGGCGACAGAGUGAGACACUGUCUUAACAAAAAAAAAUCUCCAUACUGUUUUGCAUAGAGGUUGCACUAAUUUACAUUUCCACUAGCAGUGCAUAAGUGUUCCCUUUUCACCAAGUCCAUGCCAAUAUCUAUUGUCUUUUGUCUUAAUAAUGGCCAUUCUUGCAGGAGUAAGAUGGUGUGUCAUUGUGGUUUUAAUUUGCAUUUCCCUGAAUGAUUAGUGAUAUUGAGCACUUUUUCAUUUAUGUGUUGGCCAGUUGUAUAUCUUCUUUUGAGAAAUGUUUGUUCAUGUCAUUUUCCCACUUUUUCAUGAGAUUAUUUUUUUUCUUGCUGAUUUGUUUGAGCUCCCUGUGGAUUCUGGACGUUGGUCCUUUGUUGGAUGCAUAGUUGGCGAAUAUUUUCUCCCAUUCUGUGGGUUGUCUCUUUACUCUGAUGAUGAUGCUGAUUAUUAUUUUUUGCUGUACAGAAGCCUUUUAGUUUAAUUAGGUCCCAUUUAUUUAUUUUUGUUUUAGUUGCAUUUGCUUUUGGGGUCUUAGUCAUGAAUUCUUUGCCUAGGCCAAUGUCCAGAAGAAUUUUUUUCUAGGUUAUCUUCUAGGACUUUUAUGGUUUUAGGUCUUAUAUUUAAAUCUUUGAUCUAUCUUGAGUUGAUGUUUGUAUAAGAUGAGAGACAGGGAUCCAGUUUCAUUUUUCUACUUGUGGCUAGCCAGUUUUCUCAGCACCAUUUAUUAAAUAAAUAGGGUGUCCUUUCCCCAAUUUAUGUUUUUCAUGCUUUGUUGAAGAGAGUUGGUUGUGGAUAUUUGGUUUUAUUUCUGGAUUCUUUAAUCUGUUCCAUUGGUCAAUGUGUCUAUUUUUAUACCAGUACCAUGCUGUUUUGUUAACUAUAGCCUGGUAUAAUUUGAAGUCCAAUAAUGUGAUGCCUUCAGAUUUGUUGUUUUUGUUUAGGAUUGCUUUGGCUAUUCAGCCUCUUUUUUGGUUUCAUAGGAAUUUUAGGAUUUUCUUUCUCUAAAUCUGUGAAAAAGGAUGUUGCUGUUUUGAUCAGAUUUGUAUUGAAUCUGUAGAUUGCUUUAGAUGGUAUGGUCAUUUUCAUGAUAUUGAUUCUUCCAAUCCAUGAGCAUGGGAUGUGUUUCCAUUUGUUUGUGUUAUCUAUGGUUUCUUUCAUCAGUGUUUGUAGUUCUUCUUGUAGAGAUCUUUCACCCCCUUGGUUAAGUAUAUUCCUAGGUAUUUUAUAUAUAUUUUUGCAGCUGUUAUAAAAUGGAUUGAGUUCUUAAUUUGAUUCUCAGCUUGGUCGUUGUUGUAUAGCAGUGCUACUGGAUUUGUGUUCAUUGACUUUGUAACCUAAGAUUUUACUAAAUUCACUUAUCAAAUCUAAUAGUCUUUGGAGGAAUCUUCAGCAUUUUGUAGGUAUACGAUCAUAUCAUCAGCAAACAGCGAUAGUUUGACUUCCUGUUUUCCAAUUUGGAUGCCCUUUAUUUCUUUCUCAUGCCUGAUUGCUCUGGCCAGGACUUAAAGUACUAUGUUGAAAAGAAGUGAUUAAAGUGAGCAUCCUUGUCUUAUUCCAGUUCUCAGGGGGAAUGCUUGCAACUUUUUCCCAUUCAGUAUGCUUUGUCGUAUAUGACUUUUAUUAUUUUGAGAUAAUUCCCUUCUGUGCCUUGUUUUUUGGGUGUUUUUAUCAUAAAGGGAUACUUGAUUUUAUUGAAUGUUUUUUCUGCAUCUAUUGAAACAAUCAUGUGGUUUUUGUUUUUAAUUGUUUAUGUGAUAUAUCACAUUUGUUGACUUGCAUAUGUUAAACCAUCCCUGCAUUCCUGGGAUUAAACCCACUUGAUCAUGGUGUAUUAUCUUUUUGAUGUGCCAUUUGAUUUGGUUAGCUAGUAUUUUGUUGAGGAUUUUUACAUCUAUGUUCAUCAGGGAUAUUGGUCUGUAGUUUUCUUUCUUUUUGUUACAUCCUUUCCUGGCUUUGGUAUCAGGGUGAUACUGACUUCAUAGAAUGAAGAAGAACAGGUUGCUUCCUUGAUGUGGUGCUGUCCCCCUUGCCCUAGGAGUAGGAGUCCCUGAGAGCCAGACUACUGUGAGUACUGCUGCUCCUCUGGGUCUAGCUGCCCAGUGGGGUUACCACAUUCCAGGCUGAUUCUGGGGAAUGUCUGCAAGGGAUCCAGUGAUGUUAUCUGUCCUCAAGUCUCCCAGCAAUGUGUACCAGCACCAGCUCUCAUAGGGGUAACAGGGGAAUGACAUACGUUGUGAGAUUCCUUGGUUGUAAAUAGCCGUAGUGCGUUGGCUUUCUUAAAUGCUGGUUGUAGUAUUAAUAAACUGGUCAUGUGGACAGACUCAGGACAUCCUGGUUAGCCAGGGUACUGCAGACAGUGCUGAUAACUGGGUCAUGCAUAAGUUUUCUCCUUCUUGGGUGCAAUGUUAUUUUACCUGUAGUUGCUGUAGUAAACUGUGUCUGUUGGCCUCCAGCCAGGAGGUGGUGCUUGCAAAAGAGUGCCAGCUGUGGUUGAAGUGGUGGGAUAUGUGCUUGUCUUAUGUUACCCAUGGGAGGUAUUUUGGUUUAUCAGAUGAUGGGUGAGGCCAUAGGGCUCCCCAAAGUUUCUGUCUUUUGUGUUAACCUACCAGGGCAGGUGGAGGGUCAAAGCCAGGUGGGGGGCUUGGUCAGGCAGGCCUGCUCUUUGGCUCUGCAUGUGUGGUGUAAGCACAGAUCCAUGUUGGGCUUUUGGAGCCAUUCCCUGGCCACUGGGGUAAUGUUCCAGGAAAAAGCUUAGCUGCCUCUGCUUCACAGAAGAGUUCAUGCAGGGAGUGGGGAGUAGCAGGUGGGAGUAAGUCUCAUCCAGCUCCUACACACUUGGCAAGGCAAGUCUCUCACUCAGAGUGUUCACUAGCAGCAGCUAGCUAAAUUCCAAGCUGUUUACAUACAGGAACCUCAGCUUUCAGGCCACGCCCCUUUUCAUCCACUGGCAAUGCCAGAGCACCCAACUUCUGUGUCUGUGGUUACAGCUUACUUCCCAGUCAUCCGCCCAGUUCAGCCAAGGCAGUUCAUCCCCACUUGAGAUUAUAUUUUGAAUUUCAAAUUGGGAGCUUCUUUCAACCUGCAACCACUGCCUCAGUUGGUUGGCAGAACUUUGUGAACUCUCCUGUGACACAGAAUCAGGAAUAGCUUCCCUUGGUUUGCGUUGGAGACCGGGAAUACGCACAAGGCUCUUCCCGCCCCUGGUGCUUCUUGUAUAUUCUCCACUGCUCCCUAUAUUAGUUUUAGCACUGGGUGGGGUUAAGGCCUUCCUCUGUGGGCCGGAUUUCUAGUUUUCAUAGUGGGGGUGUAUACUCUGGAGGUAAUCUCUCUCCCUCUCACACUCUGGGGACUUACAGUUUUUUACCUGGCUCAUGGUGUAGACUGCAGCCUGCCCCUUCUUUCAAAGGAUCUGUGGUUUCCGUUUUUCCAUUAAGUUCCUGCAUUGCUUCUUUGAAAAAAGUUCACAGUUUGAGUCUUUACCCACUAUUUUUUCUUUCCAAGUGGAAGAGGCAUGCCAAUACUACCUCCAAUCUGCCAUCUUGAGGAGGGUGGGAAUUUUUUUUUUAAUUAAAAUUUAAAUUUUUGUAGGCUGAUUUUGUGGCAAGGAUCAGGCUAAGGUGUAUUUAAGGUCUUCUCAGGUCUUUUCUGAGCCUGGGCAUGUGUGGUCACUUUCCACAUUUUUUCAUAUAUAUAGUUUUUGAAUGUUCUAGUCUUUAUUUUAGUUUAUUUUUUAUUUUGAGGCAGAGUCUUGCUCUGUUGCCCGGGCUGGAUUGCAGUGGCUCGAUCUUGGCUCACUGCAACCUCCGCCUCCCGAGCUCGAGCUCCUGCCUCAGCCUCCCGAGUAACUGGGAUUACAGGCGCCUGCCACCACGCUGGGCUAUUUUUUGUAUUUUUAGUAGAGACGGGGUUUCACUGUGUUGGCCAGGCUGGCCUUGAACUCCUAACCUCAAGUGAUCUUGGCCCACCUUGGCCUCCCAAAGUGCAGGGAUUACAGAUGUGAGCCACUGUGCCCAGCCAAAUGUCCUGGUCUUUAAUGUGUGGCUCUCAAAAGGGGAAAAAGAGUAAAAUGGGGUUUGCUGGCCUUUUAAGUCCCCUAGAAGUGACUUCAGCCAGAGGGGGAGAAGCUUGCAACAGUGAAGGGAGGCAUAACAAUAAUAUCUACUCAUUUCUUUGUGUGCUCCUCUGUGAUCAGAAGCAAUAAUCAGUGAUCAGAGCACAGAUCUCUGAUAUUUGGAAAAUAGUCCUUUUUGCUUACCAUGGCCCUCACAAGUUGCAUGCAGACUGUUCCAGGAACACAUGCACAGCUGUCUACCCUCGAGUUGGGGGAUGGGUGGUAGCUGAUACUGUGCUGAGAGCUAGAAUGACCGAAAUUAACCACAGUUUAUUGUUCAAGCCUUCCCUUGGAGGUUGUAAGCCUUUAGCCAGGGUUCCAAAAUAGUUACAUUAGGUAGAUUCUGCCAGUGCAAUUGUCUAGAUAGGGAUACAGAUUCCUGGUGCAUCCUACUCCAUCAUCUGAGAAUCCUCCAGCCUGGAUUCAUUCUUGACUUCUUUCUUUCUCUCAUAGCAGUCAAUCCACAUCAAUUUUGCUUGCAAAUGUCAUCCUUUUAUCUGCAAAAUACAUCUAAAGAUUGAUCACUUUUUUUUUUUUUUGAGACAAGGUCUCACUCUGUCGCCCAAACUGGAGUGCAGUAGAGAGAUCUUGGAUCACUGCAGCUUCAACCUGCCCAGCGUCCCGAGUAGCUGGGACAAAGGGGUGUGCCAUCAUGCUUGGCUAUGAUCACUUUUUCACUACCUCCAGAACUACCACUCUGGUCCCAGCCUGUAUCACUUCUCAUCUCAUUAUGGGUUUGUGCAAAAGUAGUUUGCAUUACAUUAAAAGUAAUGGCAAAACUGCAAUUACUUUUGCACAACAUAUAUUAUUGCAGCCUGCUAACUGACCCCCGUUUCUGCUGUUGUCCCCUUGUCUGUUCUCAACCCAGCAUCUGAAUGAUCCUUAUAAUAAUCAGAUCAUCUUUUUGUGUAAAACCUUUCUUCUCUCUGAAGUCAAAGUCCUUACAGGGGACCUACUUGGCUCCCUUCCCUUACCUUUCUGUCCUCUUCUUCAACUAUUCUUUCUUCCUCUUGCUCACUUCACUUCAGCUGUAUUGGGUCCCCUUGCCGGUCCUUUAACUAGUCAGGCAUACAUCCUCUUGAGGGUGUUGAAUUUCUUUUGACUAGAAGGCUCUUGUGCCAGGCAUUGCCACAACUCACUUCUACUUUUGGGUUUUUACUCAUAUGUCACUUUUUUAGUGAGUCCUUAUCUGACCACUCAAUCUGAAUUGGCAGCUCUCCCUGCCAAAUAAUCCCUAUCUCUUUGGUUAAUUUAACUCCUUAGCCUUCAUCACCAUCUACAGGUAUGGUGUACUAUUUUAUUUUUUUCUCUCUCCUCUGCAGUGUAAGAUCCAUAAAAACAGGGACUUUGCCUUUAUUCACUACUGGACCCGGGCACCUAAAAUUGUGCUAUCAUAUAAUAGUGCUCAUUUAGUGUUUGUGUGAUUGAAUUAAUGAAUGGAGUGCUUGGGUUAUCCUGGCAUCAGUGCUUAGUAUUUAUGUAUACCUUAUCUAAUUUCAAUGAAGUAGAGGCAAUAAAACAUCUAGUAGACAAAUCUGGAAGAGAGAGUUGAGUGAAGCUGUAGGAGUAGAUUUCAUAGCUUAGAAAGAGUGUAAAGAAUCUGAAGAGAAAAGGACUAGGGAUGGGAUCCUGGAAACACCCGCCUGUAAGGGUUGACCAGAGAGCAGCACUGUCCUAAGACUUCACCAACUGGCAACAAAAGACCUGUGCUUUAAAGGUCCUCAUAUGGCCUUCCUCCAGCAGCUACAACCCUACCCAUAGAGUGAAGACUUUGUGGGGGGCCAAGGUGACUAGACUAGUCUACCUGGUCUCUUUCUAGAUCAGUCUUUGAAUAUUUGAUCCUAGAAUUUCCUGCCCAUGUGUCCCUUCACAACUGUCUUCUCUGAUUCUUUCCUCUCUUGACUGUACAACACAUAUGGGAUCCCCUGUGUUUAAGGGAUGGCCAAGGAGCAGCUGUUUGCAGUCAUGUGACCAGAGCUUGGACCUGUAGGCUUUAUAUAUGUGUGCAUAUGAAGUCCUUCGUAUAAAGUGGAGCUAAAAGUGGGAAGAGAAAAGGAGUUGGCUGCAGACAAGGGGAAGGGUUCCAAAGAACUACUGGUUCAGAUUUUAGCUCUUCCCAAGUUGUGAAAAUAGUGAAGGAUGCUUAGACUACUUAACAUACAAACUGCUUUCUGGUUAAUCAUCUUUAGAAGACUGGAUUUCUGGAUAUCUACUCCACUCCAUCUCUAUUGACUUUUAAAACAUGAUAAUGCAAACCUAUAACACUGGCAACCAUCAGUGAACCUUUAAUUUCAUUGAUUAAUAGCGUUUGAAGCUUCCUCAGGGAAUAACAAUGACAUCAGCAGUGGUUGACAGUGGAGGUACUAUUUUGGAGCUUUCCAGCAAUGGAGUAGAAAAUCAAGAGGAAAGUGAAAAGGUUUCUGAAUAUCCAGCAGUGAUUGUGGAGCCAGUUCCAAGUGCCAGAUUAGAGCAGGGCUAUGCAGCCCAGGUUCUGGUUUAUGAUGAUGAGACUUAUAUGAUGCAAGAUGUGGCAGAAGAACAAGAAGUUGAGACCGAGAAUGUGGAAACAGUGGAAGCAUCAGUUCACAGCAGUAAUGCACACUGUACAGAUAAGACAAUUGAAGCUGCUGAAGCCCUGCUUCAUAUGGAAUCUCCUACCUGCUUGAGGGAUUCAAGAAGUCCUGUGGAAGUGUUUGUUCCUCCUUGUGUAUCAACUCCAGAAUUCAUCCAUGCUGCUAUGAGGCCAGAUGUCAUUACAGAAACUGUAGUGGAGGUGUCAACUGAAGAGUCUGAACCCAUGGAUACCUCUCCUAUUCCAACAUCACCAGAUAGCCAUGAACCAAUGAAAAAGAAAAAAGUUGGCCGUAAACCAAAGACCCAGCAAUCACCAAUUUCCAAUGGGUCUCCUGAGUUAGGUAUAAAGAAGAAACCAAGAGAAGGAAAAGGAAACACAACCUAUUUGUGGGAGUUUCUUUUAGAUCUACUUCAAGAUAAAAAUACUUGUCCCAGGUAUAUUAAAUGGACUCAGAGAGAAAAAGGCAUAUUCAAGCUGGUGGAUUCAAAGGCUGUCUCUAAGCUUUGGGGAAAGCAUAAGAACAAACCAGACAUGAACUAUGAAACCAUGGGACGAGCUUUGAGAUACUACUACCAAAGGGGAAUUCUUGCAAAGGUUGAAGGACAGAGGCUUGUAUAUCAGUUCAAGGAUAUGCCGAAAAACAUAGUGGUCAUAGAUGAUGACAAAAGUGAAACCUGUAAUGAAGAUUUAGCAGGAACUACUGAUGAAAAAUCAUUAGAACGAGUGUCACUGUCUGCAGAAAGUCUCCUGAAAGCAGCAUCCUCUGUUCGCAGUGGAAAAAAUUCAUCCCCUAUAAACUGCUCCAGAGCAGAGAAGGGUGUAGCUAGAGUUGUGAAUAUCACUUCCCCUGGGCACGAUGCUUCAUCCAGGUCUCCUACUACCACUGCAUCUGUGUCAGCAACAGCAGCUCCAAGGACAGUUCGUGUGGCAAUGCAGGUACCUGUUGUAAUGACAUCAUUGGGUCAGAAAAUUUCAACUGUGGCAGUUCAGUCAGUUAAUGCAGGUGCACCAUUAAUAACCAGCACUAGUCCAACAACAGCGACCUCUCCAAAGGUAGUCAUUCAGACAAUCCCUACUGUGAUGCCAGCUUCUACUGAAAAUGGAGACAAAAUCACCAUGCAGCCUGCCAAAAUUAUUACCAUCCCAGCUACACAGCUUGCACAGUGUCAACUGCAGACAAAGUCAAAUCUGACUGGAUCAGGAAGCAUUAACAUUGUUGGAACCCCAUUGGCUGUGAGAGCACUUACCCCUGUUUCAAUAGCCCAUGGUACACCUGUAAUGAGACUAUCAAUGCCUACUCAGCAGGCAUCUGGCCAGACUCCUCCUCGAGUUAUCAGUGCAGUCAUAAAGGGGCCAGAGGUUAAAUCGGAAGCAGUGGCAAAAAAGCAAGAACAUGAUGUGAAAACUUUGCAGCUAGUAGAAGAAAAACCAGCAGAUGGAAAUAAGACAGUGACCCACGUAGUGGUUGUCAGUGCGCCUUCAGCUAUUGCCCUUCCUGUAACUAUGAAAACAGAAGGACUAGUGACAUGUGAGAAAUAAAAUAGCAGCUCCACCAUGGACUUCAGGCUGUUAGUGGCAGUACUGACAUAAACAUUUGCAAGGGAAGUCAUCAAGAAAAGUCAAAGAAGACUUUAAAACAUUUUUAAUGCAUAUACAAAAACAAUCAGACUUACUGGAAAUAAAUUACCUAUCCCAUGUUUCAGUGGGAAAUGAACUACAUAUUGAGAUGCUGACAGAAAACUGCCUCUUACAGUAGGAAACAACUGAACCCAUCAAUAAGAAAAAGGAUCGAAAGGGACCAAGCAGCUCACUACGAUAUCAAGUUACACUAAGACUUGGAACACUAACAUUCUGUAAGAGGUUAUAUAGUUUUCAGUGGGAGGGGUUGGGAUGGGUAAUCUCAUUGUUACAUAUAGCAAUUUUUGAUGCAUUUUAUAUGCAUACCAGCAAUUAUUACUGUGUUCGCACAGUUCUCACUUAACUGGUGCUAUGUGAAGACUCUGCUAAUAUAGGUAUUUUAGAAUGUGAAUUGAAGAAUGGAUCCCAAAAACUUCAGAAAGAGGAUAGCAAAAAAAGAUCUAGUGCGAUUUUAUAUAUAUAUAUAUAUAUAUAUACAUACAUAUAUAUAUAUCAUAUAGCUUAAGCUGAUUUAAAACAAAGGCCUUAGACUAAUUUUCGAUUUUCUUUCUUGAAAUAAGCUAAUGGCUUGUUUGUGUAAAGCUUUUUUAUUAAAAGAAAAAUUUUAAAAAUCUUGUACCUAGCACAGUAUUGUUAUAGAAUAUACAUGUAACAUUUUAUAUGGUAGUUUAAGUCUGUCAGUUUCUUAAUUGUGGACAAAUUAACAGUUGGCUCUGGCCUUUUGCUGUAACAUGCCUGUGUCACUCACUUAGCCUUGGCAUUUGUGCAGACAUACCAUUUUCAGUUCUGCUGUCACUUGGAAGUUCAGGCUCAGCAUGAAUUUUUGGCAGGUAGCUCUAAUACCUGGAGUUUUCUUUGUUUUUUUUUCUUUUUUUUAGUUGAAGUUUAUGAGGGAAAUACCAGUGUUCAGUUUUGAACUAUAAUAGUUUGUAUAUUCAACAUUUGAAGUAUAUUCUAUUUUGUUGUACUCUUGUUUCAAAGUGUAUUCAAGUAGGUUUUCUGAAAUAUAGAAAUGAAAUUUAUCUUCUGUUUUGGUCUCUGGUGAUAUUUUAAACAAUAUUUAAAAGUCAGUAUAGAAGUGUUUUAGUUAGGAAGUGAUAAAACAUCUCUCUUCUCCUUCCCAACUACUGCAUGAAGAAAUUCUACUUCCAUUAUAUUAAUAUUUGGCAAAUAUCUGCAUGUUGCCAGUUUCUUUCUAAUUAUGAUGAACUAUAAUGUUCUGCUUAACGUAAUGAAUUUAGUAUUUUAGUUGGCUGCACUUAAAGAAUUUAUAUUUGUAAAACACUUUAAACCAUUUGUUUCACAAUCAGACCUUUUGUGGAUUAAAAAGAACAAUUACUCUUCUAGCCCUUUUACAGAUUAGGAAGUUAAGGUAUCUGAAGGAUUACAUAAACUAUGUAAUUUUACUACUGUCUGUCACUCCAUAUCUUAAUGCUCUUUCUACUACAAAGAAAAGUUAUCUAUUUUUACAUGUUUUAGAAAUGUAGAUGAACUCAUACAUAAUAUUUUUUGUCUUUUAAUUGAUCACAUACUACUUAGGUCAGAAAUUGUUUAUAACAGUUCCCUUUGUAAUCUUUUAAACUUUUCCAUAAAUAUAUUGAUGAUACUUUUAUACAAAAGCUCAAAGAAAAACUCACUUGAUUAUUUUCCCAUUUGGGAGUUAC